ACUCCUUCCCUCCGCGUUCCGGGCCUCGGAGCCGCCUUGAGGAGGAUGAGUCCCUGGAGCUGGUUCCUGCUGCAGACCCUCUGCCUCCUGCCCACGGGCGCAGCUUCGCGGCGCGGGGCGCCCGGCACCGCCAACUGCGAGCUCAAGCCCCAACAAAGCGAGCUGAAUUCCUUCUUGUGGACCAUUAAGCGAGACCCACCAUCUUACUUCUUUGGCACAAUCCAUGUCCCGUACACCCGAGUUUGGGACUUCAUCCCCGACAACUCUAAGGAGGCUUUCCUGCAGAGCAGCAUUGUGUACUUUGAGUUGGAUCUCACAGACCCCUAUACCAUCUCAGCUCUCACCAGCUGUCAGAUGCUGCCACAGGGCGAGAACCUCCAAGAUGUGCUCCCCAGGGACAUCUACUGCCGCCUCAAGCGCCACCUGGAGUAUGUCAAGCUCAUGAUGCCCUUGUGGAUGACCCCAGACCAGCGCGGCAAGGGGCUCUACGCAGACUACCUCUUCAAUGCUAUUGCCGGAAACUGGGAGCGCAAGAGGCCUGUCUGGGUGAUGCUCAUGGUCAACUCCCUGACUGAAGUGGACAUUAAGUCCCGUGGAGUGCCUGUCUUAGACCUGUUCCUUGCCCAGGAGGCUGAGCGGCUGAGGAAACAGACUGGGGCAGUGGAAAAGGUGGAAGAGCAGUGCCAUCCAUUGAAUGGGUUGAACUUUUCACAGGUCAUCUUUGCUUUGAACCAGACCCUCCUGCAGCAGGAAAGCCUGCGAGCAGGCAGUCUUCAGAUCCCCUACACGACGGAGGAUCUCAUCAAACACUAUAACUGCGGGGACCUCAGCUCCGUCAUCCUCAGCCAUGACAGCUCCCAGGUUCCCAAUUUUAUUAAUGCCACGCUACCACCUCAGGAGCGCAUCACUGCUCAGGAGAUUGACAGCUACUUACGCCGGGAGCUGAUCUACAAGCGGAAUGAGAGAAUAGGGAAGCGGGUGAAGGCCCUUUUGGAGGAGUUCCCUGACAAAGGCUUCUUCUUUGCCUUUGGAGCUGCUUCACAGUAGCCUUGAAAAUCAGGAGCCUUGAACUACAGUAGCUGUGAAAACUGUUUGCCUAAUGGUUACUGGAGGGGACAGAAUGGGUUCAAAGUUCCUCCAAAGCUCCAUCCUUAAAGAAUCAUCACUAUUUGACAUGUCCAAUAGUUCCCUGAAAUUUCCAUUCCCAAGCUUGUCUUCAUUUGACCUGACUCAGAGCUUGCUCUGUGUGAAUAGCCCUAUUCUUAGGGUGUGUGUUGAAAACAAUCAGUAGCAGCUGUUUAACAUCAUAGUUGCUGGAAAUAGCAAUAUUAAUUGAAGCUUACAAGGGGCUGCCCAAAAAACUUAAAAGCAAAAUCCCAUAGGGGGUAUAGAAAAGCUCUAAAAUAUUCCUAGAGAGUCACAUGCAUGAGAAGAGCUGUGCACAUGCCCAGGAAAGACCUGAGAAGGUCCUAAUCUCUCACCUCUGGCUGAUCUUGAGGCUCUGUGUAAGCAGAGUGUGAAAGCUAAGGCAAAGUCAUAAAUUGCCUGUUGAAGCAUCAAAUACAUGCCCCCAAACUCACACAGCCCCUCUGCAAAGGUUGGGAAACUUGCAAGGAAUUUAAGGAAAUCUCUGUUCAGUCAUUAGCCAGCCACUAAACUAACUGAGCAGAUCCUUCAGUGAUCACACACAACAAAGAAUACAGACUUUACAGACUUAGUCCUAGAAAAUCACUACACAAACAGCAACAACAAUGCACCUGGGACUAAGGGAGAGGAGAUGAGUUCCAGAGUUGGUAUAUUAUUUAAAUGUCUAGUUUUCAAUAAAAACAAUUAUAAGACACAGAGCAAAACUAGAAAGUAUGGCCCAUACCCAGGGAAAAACAAGCAACCAAUAGAAGCUGUCCUUGAGGAAGUUAAUAUCUUGGACUUACUAGAAAAUGACUUUAACACUAGUUAUUAUAAAUAUGUUCAAAAAACUAAAAGAGGCCAGGUGCGGAGGCUCACGCCUAUAAUCCCAGCACUUUGGGAGGCUGAAGCAGGUGGGUCACCUGAGGUCAGGAGUUUGAGACCAGCCUGACCAAUAUGGCAAAACCCUAUCUCUACUAAUAAUACAAAAAUUAGCCAGGCGUUGUGGCGCACACCUGUAAUCCCAGCUACUUGGGAGGCUGAAGCAGGAGAACUGCUUGAAACUGGGAGGAAGAGGUUGCAGUAAGCUGAGAUCACACCACUGUACUCCAGCCUGGGCCACAAGAGUGAAACUCCAUCUCCAAAAAAAAAAAAAAAAAAAAAAACCCUAAAAUUAACCAUAUCUAAAGAAUUAAAGGAAAGUUUGAGAACAAUAUCUCACCAAUACAGAAUAUCAAUAAAAAUAUAAAAAUUAUUUUAAAAGAACCAAAUAGGAAUUCUGGAAUUUAAAGUGUAGGAACUGAAAUGAAAAAUUCACUACGGGGGCUGAACAGUAGAUUUGAACUGGCAGAAGAAGAAUCAACAUACAUGAAGAUAGGUUGAUUGAGAUGAUUCAGUAUGAGAAAGAGAAAGGAAAAGGAAUGAAGAAAAAUGAAUAGAUCUUCAGAUACCUGUGAGACACCCUCAAGUGUGCCAAUGUAUACCUAACGGGAGUCCCAGAAGACAGGAGAGAAAAAAAGAAAGAAAUAAAAAGAAUAUUUGAAUUUAAAAUUGCUUGAAAAUGUCUCAAAUUUGAUGAAAAAUAUUACUCUGCACAUUCAACCCAUGAACUAUAAGUUGUAUAAAAUCAAAAAGUUUCACACCAAGGCGUGUCAUAGCCAAACUGUCAAAAGCCAAAGACACAGAAUCUUGAAAGCAGUGAGAGCAAAGCAGACAAGGGAUCCCCAAUAGGAUUAACAGCAGAUUUCUCAUCAGAAGCCAUGCAAGCCAGAAGGCUAUGGGAGACAUACUCAAAAUGCUGAAAUAAAAGACUGUCAACAAACAUUUCCACAUCCAGCAAAAAUCAAAAACGAAGGAGAAAUCUGUUGCAUGUGAGCUGAAUAGAAUUUGUAUUCUGCUGUUGUUGGAUGAAGUAUUCUUUAAAUGUCAAUUAGAUCAAUUUGAUUGAUGAUGCUCUUCAGUUCAACUAUAUUCCCUAUCUGAUAAUUCCAGAAUCUCUAUCAUGUCUGAGUCUGGGUCUGAUGCUUUCAUUGUUUCUUCAGAUUGUGAUUUUUCUUGCCUCCCAGUGUGACUUGUAAUUUUUAAUUGAAAGCUGGAUAUGAUGUAUUUGGCAAUGGGAAGUGAGGGAAAUAUGUUUUUAGUGUGAGGGUUUAUGUUAAUCUUUCUCAGAGUUGGGCUGUUUAAUGUUUUGCUGUGGUCUGAAUGUUCCUUAAAACUUGUGUGUUGAAACUUAA